GUUUCAGUGGCUUCUGGUGCUCUAGGGUGAGCUCUGCCCGGCUGCAGGGAUGGCGGGGAGGGGUAAGCUCAUCGCAGUGAUCGGAGACGAGGACACGGUGACUGGUUUCCUGCUGGGCGGCAUAGGGGAGCUUAACAAGAACCGCCAUCCCAAUUUCCUGGUGGUGGAGAAGGAUACAACCAUCAAUGAGAUCGAAGACACUUUCCGUUCACUUGGAAGCCUUCCGGGCAGUGUUGUAGAAGCCAACCCUAAUCAGCGUGACCCUCCGCUUUGGGAUGAAAUUGAUUCUAGGCAAUUUCUAAACCGGGAUGACAUUGGCAUCAUCCUCAUCAACCAGUACAUCGCAGAGAUGGUGCGGCAUGCCCUGGACGCCCACCAGCAGUCCAUCCCCGCUGUCCUGGAGAUCCCCUCCAAGGAGCACCCAUAUGACGCCGCCAAGGACUCCAUCCUGCGCAGGGCCAGGGGCAUGUUCACUGCCGAAGACCUGCGCUAGGGGACUCCUCAUAGCCCUCAGCCCUUCCCUCGUUUCCAGGCCUCUCCCCAGGCUUGCCAUCAGCCUUCUUUACUUUUUGAGCCUCUGAUUUCCAAUUCCCUGCUCCUUCCCACUCCAUUAAGAGGCUAGGUGAGGCGCUUCUAGGUUGCUGGGGCUCUGCUGGUUAAGGAACAGGAAGCCUGACCAUCUCCCUCCACUACCUCUUCCCUGUGCUGUUACACAGUGUCAUUGUUGAUGUUAAAUUAAAGUCAUAUUCUUGCUUCUCUCCA